GGCUUCCCCGCCCCGCCCCGUCCCCGGGCGUCUCCAUUUUGGUCUCAGGUGUGGACUCGGCAAGAACCAGCGCAAGAGGGAAGCAGAGUUAUAGCUACCCCGGCCGCGGAGCCGGCUCACUGCACUACCCCCGCCCCCUUCUUUCCUCCAGACGCCGAAGUCGCGGGCGCUCAUGGCGGGCCUGGAGGUACUGUUCGCAUCGGCAGCGCCGGCCAUCACCUGCAGGCAGGACGCGCUCGUCUGCUUCUUGCAUUGGGAAGUGGUGACACACGGUUACUUCGGCUUGGGUGUCGGUGACCAGCCGGGUCCCAAUGAUAAGAAGUCAGAACUGCUGCCAGCUGGGUGGAACAACAAUAAAGACCUGUAUGUCCUCCGGUAUGAGUAUAAGGAUGGGUCCAGAAAGCUCCUUGUGAAAGCCAUCACCGUGGAGAGCAGCAUGAUCCUCAAUGUGCUGGAAUAUGGCUCACAGCAAGUGGCAGACUUGACCCUGAACUUGGAUGAUUAUAUCGAUGCAGAACACCUGGGUGACUUCCACAGGACCUACAAGAACAGUGAGGAGCUUCGGUCUCGUAUUGUGUCUGGAAUCAUCACACCUAUCCAUGAGCAGUGGGAAAAGGCUAAUGUAAGCAGUCCCCACCGGGAGUUCCCCCCUGCUACCGCCAGAGAGGUGGACCCACUCCGGAUUCCUCCACACCACCCACACACCAGUCGGCAGCCUCCCUGGUGUGAUCCCCUGGGCCCGUUUGUUGUCGGGGGAGAAGACUUAGACCCUUUUGGGCCUCGGAGAGGUGGCAUGAUUGUGGAUCCCCUGAGAUCUGGCUUCCCAAGAGCACUUAUUGACCCUUCCUCAGGCCUCCCGAACCGACUUCCUCCAGGCGCUGUGCCCCCAGGAGCUCGCUUUGACCCCUUUGGACCCAUUGGGACCAGCCCACCCGGGUACGUAGUCACUCAGACCUAACCCAGACCAUCUCCCCCCGCCGGGCUACGAUGACAUGUACCUGUGAAGGCCUCAAGAAUGUAACAUCCCAGGCUUCCCUCCAUUCUCCUGGAGCUGCCACCGCUGUCCCCAUCAGCAACCAUGUUCUUGCAGGCUGGGGGCAAGGGAUUCUGCUCAUGUGUUUGCAGACCGGCUGGGAUAGCCUCCCCACCCCUUAUCAGAGCCAAGACACCUGCUGCAGCUCUCCACCUAGCUGCAGAUAGCUCCCAAAGAGAAAUCAGUGUGUCUCUUUCACCAUCAGCUCCUCCCCUUUCACCACCAGCUCCUCUCCACUUCCCAAGGGAGACUCCGGCAACCUUCAGCAACAUAUAUCCUCGACCAGAUGCAGUGCUAUAAGAACAGAACGCAUUUUGGAUGUUAUUAUUAAGAACCAAAUGUCAAUACAGAAUUCAUGUUGCCGGUUUCCCACUUUUCUUUUUACAUUAAUGCAUAGCUGCUUCCAUUUAUGAGACUUUAGAGUUUGAGUUUCUGUAGGGCUGAAUGACUCUUUUUCCUGCCCAGGGCCCAUUCUUGCUUCUCAGGCACCUUCCGUUUAUUAAUUGCCAUUGCUCCUGACAUCACUAAGAUGGGUCCCCUUCUGGCUGCAUGAAUGGAAAUGAGUGACUGGAAAUCCCAUAGGCCACAAGAAUGACUUUCACAAGGGCAGGAACAUUGUGGAAAGACUGCAUCAUUCUGAUGAGGCAAAAUCCUCCAGCUAUUCCUGUCUGGGCCAGUUUUGUAGGUCCAUCUGUGCAUGGGCAGCAGUAGUCAAAAAGCCAAGGAAAAAACAGAGCAGACCUGAAGGCUAAUCUUAUUUUUGCCACUAACUUAGUGAAUGACCCUAAGCAAGUUCCUUCUCCUCUUAGGGCCUUGUGCCAAGCCUAUGAAAUUGGAGGUGGCUUUCCUGCUCUAAAGCAUUUUGAUGUCUCAUUCUGUGUUUGGUAACCCCUAUAAACUGGGGCAGAGGAAAAGAAUGAUGGUUCAAGGCCAUACUUCCCUUGAACCUUGUGUGGUUCUUGCCUAACUCUGUGGUUUUUGGACCCCAUGGGGCCCAGACAGAGCACAGGAGCAUGGGCUGCCUCUGAGUGUGGUGUUGAACUUCGGGAGGAGCAGGGAGCCCUGCACCUUGUGUCCUGGCCCACCUGACCUUUGGUGUUCUCCGGAUCCUUUUCAGCCCGAGGCCUGACAGACGCGGGCAGUGAUGAGCCCUGUUCUGGAGUGGAAAGAGCACGAUAGAGCACCAGGCUAAGAGGCACGAGAUCAAGGCGGUAGUCACUUCCGCUCUGCAGCUAGCAUUUCAACCAUAUGUGGAUCCUUUCAUUUCUCAGCUCCCUGGAUUCCUUCCCCUAAAUUAGGACCUAUUAUUUACCUGUAGGUAAGCAAGCUACUGUAGCUCUUCUGAGGUAUCUGCCAGGCUGUUUUCUGUAGCCUCAGAUUGCCUAUCUGCUUAGCCUGAGAACAGGUAGAUGAAAACUAAACUGAUGCCUAGGCCCAGGGUCAGUCUCAGAUGGAAGCUGGGCCUGGGUGGGGAGGCUAGCAUGCGUGGCUCCCUGGGUAUUUCUGUCAGUCCCCAUGGCAAGCAGUGAUUUAGUAAAACACCCCAGAGUCAGGGAAGCCAACCACCUUGAAACCUUUAGAACAUCUCUGCUUUGGAGAAAGACCCAGAGAUCAGGCAGAGGUGCAGAUUCAAUCAUUACUCAUAACCUUUGAGAGAUGGCAAAUGGGAGGAGUGUUAGUCUUUGUUUUGGAAUUGGACCAUUCUUGCAACCAAAAGGACUUAGAGCAGUUUGCUCAUAAAGACAUCCUUUAUUAUAAAAGGAAGUAUUUAAAGGAUGAUAGAGACCAUCAGAUAGAAGCAGGGAAGGUAGAUAACUUUUAGGACCUUGAUGUGAGGAAAAGAUAAAAUUUAAACAAUAAAUUUGCCACUUAGAUUUUCUAGCAGCAAAGUCCGAAAAGAUAGUUAUAUACAAAAUUCUGUUUUCUGAAAACAAAAUUGUGAUUCACCUUCAGAAUUGGCCAUUUUUUUUGUGAGUUUCCUUGCAUCAAGGACACUGAGAAACACAGUCAUUGUCUUAGGUGUUCUAUGGGAGGAAGUGAAUAGAGCCUUUAGGAACUUCCUGGUCAAGCUUAUGGUGCUUAUUUUGAUCUGGGCCACUUCCCUCCUUCCAGUCAUGAGUAAUCAUCAAGGAGCAAGUUGGAGUGUUUCAGGUGUAUAUUUUGUAGAACCCAAAAGAUUGGAGCCUUAACAAUAAACAUCAGCACUAAGUGACCUGUUCCUCCUUUUUUAAAUAGCAGCUUUAUUGAGAUAUAAUUUACAUACCCAUAAUUUACAUACCUGUUUAAAGUAUACAAUUCAGUGGAUUUAGUAUGUUCACAGUGUUGCACAUCCACCACCAUUUCUAAUUCCUGAACAUUUUCACCACCUCAAAAAGAAACCACACACCCAUUGGCAUGACUCCCCAUUCCCUUGCUCCCAGCCCCAGGCAACCACUAACAUCUGUCUCUAAAGAUUUUUUUUUUUUUUCUGGACAGUUCUCAUAAGUGGAAUCACUCAGUAUUAUGGCCUUUUGUGUCUGGCUUCUUUCAUUUCAUGUGAUGUUUUCAAGAUUCAUUCAUGCUGUAGCAUGUAUCCAUGGUAUGGAUAUAUCACAUUUUGCUUAUCCUUUUAUCAGUUGAUGGACAGUUGGGUUGUUUCUACAAAAAGGCUAUUAUGAGUAAUGCAGCCAAGAACAUUUGUGUACCAGUUUUUGAGUUUUCAGUUGUUUGAGUUUCAGAUGUUUUCAGUUCAUUUGGGUAUAUACCAAGGAGUGGAAUUGCUGGUUCACAUGGUAGCUCUAUAUUCUACUUUGUGAGGAAUUGUCAGACUGUUUUCCACGGAAGCUGCACCAUUUUACAUUUCCACUGGUAAUUUAUGAGGGUUCCAGUUUCCCCACAUCUUCACCAACUCUUGUUAUUUUUCAUGCUUAUGGCCAUCCUAGUUAGCGUGAAGUAGCAUCUCAUUGUGGUCUUCUCUUCCAUUUUUUAAAAAAGAAUUUUGACCUACACCAAGCAAGGCAGAGACCAGAGUCAGUCCCCCUUGGGGAGCAAUCUGUGGUUUUGAUAAUCACCACCUUGGGAUGAACAUGGCUGGUGAGCUGCAGAGCAGUUGAUUUGACUUUUGGGGAUGGUUCUAGGCUGGAUGUGAUACAGGGCAGGUUUUGUCUCUAGAGAAAGUUCUCAUGACCUUCAGGUCUAAUGAGAUUCAGAUCAUCACUUUGGUUUGGUUUGAAAUUUCUUUGUUUAUCCAGUGAAUUACAAGUAGAAUAAAGAUCUGGUUCUAAAUUGUCUUUUGGUGGUGAAGUGCCAUAGACCAUUUCGGACCAUUUCUAUGAUGUACCAGCAGCCCCCACAUCACACCUCCUCUUCCUUGGCUUGUCUCUUCCCCAAUUCUUAGAGUUAGCAGUGUUUCUUACUGCAUUCAUCUCCUCAGUCAUAAGUGUCUGUCAACCUCCGUUGUGAAGUCAUGAGUCUCUUGAGACUGAAACUCCAAGAAUGUAUUGUGCUCACAGUGGCGAUGGUGUUCCUGUGCUGGAUGGUCAGUGGUUGUUGACAUGUAGUUAGAAAAUAGGUAGCAAGUUCCACGCAGCCUCACUCUUUGGAACCUAGUUUCUCCUAUGGCCUCCCUUUCUACUGUUGUUAAUAACAUUCUAUUAAUGAUCCAUGCCUCUCUUCACAGGAGGAAUAUUAGAAUCUAUGGAGCAGUUAGUAUUCUUUGUCACCUAAAUUUGUCUACUUCUGUACAUUUCCAAUAAGGCACCACCAGGGCAAGGGAAGAUUCCCCACAUGUAUAUCCCCAGCUGUUUCUGUCAUAAAACUUGCAUGUGUAUAAACCACUAUUGACUUUUUGCACCAAAGGAGAUAUUCAAGGACAGACAUCCAAGUCCCCAGCCCUUUAUUGCCCUUGGGAUACCACAAGGCACAGAUACAGGCAGCUGCUGUGUGGCUCUGGAGUUCCUAAUCCCCAGAUUGUAGCAAUGAUGAUGUGAUCCUGCUGCUCUCUGGACCGUAACCUUUUUGGUUACAAAAGGUAAAUUUCUGUUUACUGCAUCUGAACCCCAGGACUAAUGCGUCACUGCAUUAACCCCAGGACACAUGGACCAAGUCACUGCGGCCGUACUUGGCCCUGAAUCUGUCCUGGAGGGUGGGUCAAAAGGCAAGGGUGGCAGGUAGGAUGGUAGGCAGUGAGGGGUGGCAAGGCCUAGCUGACUGAGGACAGACCCAGCAACAAUGACAGGAGGUUUGAACACCUCACGAGUGGUAGUGCCCAUGGGAGGUGCGAAGUGGAAGGCCCAGCCCUUGCUUGGAGGAACGUGAGGCUGAUGGUGCAGUGCAAUAGAGGUCACUGGAUGCCCAUUUGAACAGCUGCGUUCCAGAUGAGCCACCUAAGGUGGAUGUUGUGAGAGUCACAGUGGGUUUAGAGGGACAAGGUAGUGAGAGGAUGCUGCUGACGCAUUAGUCCUGGGAUUCAGCUGCAGUAAACAGAAAUUUACCUUUUGUAACCAAAAAGGUAAUGGUCCAGAGAGCAGCAGGAUCACAUCAUCAUUGCUACAAUCUGGGGAUUAGGAACUCCAGAGCCACACAGCAGCUGCCUAUAUCUGCACCAAAAAGUAGAUGUCCUUCACACUGCCAUCUGGACACCACUCAGCUAGCUCAUCCAAGUUCAAGGCUCAAUUGAAUGCGUCUGGUUGUUGGAACCUACAUGGCCUCUCAAAUGGUACUGGCAUGGAAUAUUGGGGAGAUGUCUUUAUUCCCUCUUCCCACCUUUCCUGGAAGGUGCACUGGGACAGAGGUCUAGUGAGCCAAUCUUCUGUGUUGUCUACGCCAUGGACCAUGAUAUAAAUGGGUACCACAGCCUUGCAUGCCUGAGCCUAACCAUCUCCUGAGAUGCUUGCUCUAAGUACACAUUAGUACAUGCUGGGCCCCAAUCUAGAUCUCAAGGGAACGGCCUUCAGAUCCAUUUUUGACAAGUUCCUUUUGUGAGUCCUAUGAUCAUGCAAGUUUGAGAACUGAGAAGGGAGGGGAAGACCUACCUCCUUGUUACUCAGACCACCAGCAACAGCAGCAUCACCUGGGAACCUGUUACACAUGCAGAAUCUCAAGCCCCACCCCAGACAUUGAAUGAGAAUCUGCAUUUUAACAAGUUCUCCAUGAGAUUUGUGUAAACUUAAAGUGAGAGAAGCUCACAUGGACUAUGUCUUUUUCCUUUACGUGAAUAUCGAGUACAAAGAAUUGAGCCAGUCAGUCCUCUUGGUUAAUGGCACAUUAUGAUUAAUGCAUGCAUGAACUCUGAUUCGAAGUUUUCGUUGAUUUUACCCCCAGUAUCCACUCCAUUCCUUUGCCCCCAUGGGUCACUUAGAUGUGUUUCAUGUUAUCUUUAAAAAUGCAGCACCUUUAUAGCAUACAUUAUAUCUUCAAACCAUAACCAUAAUGAGGUGUUAUCCCCAUUUCCUGUACCAGAAAAGGAAGGAUUGGGAAGGUCCAGUAAUUUGCUCAGGGUCAAGCAGGAGUCUCAGACUCAGUCAAGCGUGGUUACUCACAGCCCUCCCUUUCUCAGUGUGUGGCCUUCCUCAUCCACAAAAUGAGCAUCACCCCUACCUGCAGGAUUCUUGCAAGAUCCAACCAAAUAAUGUGUCUUAUUAACAGAGAGUUGGGGCUCGGUGGGUGCUUGCUGCAAUUGUUACUAAAGUCAUAUGGGUAGAUAAGGGUGGGACUCAAGGACAAGAGAGGAACCUUGGAAUAUCCCCCAGUGCAGGAAACAAGCAUUUAUCAGGUGCACACAGCGUGCUAGGCUUCUCCUCAUCGCAUGUAGUACCCCUGACAACCCCAAGGUAAACACAGCUAGUGGCAUUAGUUGAGAUGCUGCACCUACCCCCUGGGGUGGCAGAACCGUGAUUGGAACCCAGGUCAGUGCUCUUUUCAGUAGAACUGCUGUACCCAGACCUCACAUCCUCUCUAGGUGAGGUGCAUGGGUCCCUGGGCAAAACCCAUUCCAGAAGCUGGGAAACCACGUCAGGACUUGUGUGAGAAAGGAGUGAUGCUUCAUAAUCCCCAGGAUGGUCUUAAGGCUCCUCAGUCAGUCCUAUUUGCACAGCGUGCCUCAUGCUCCUGAGUACCUCCACCUGCAGCCACAGUGCCCAGAGCACCUGGUUAGGAGGAGCAUCUGAAACCACCUGCACAACCUCCAUUCCACAGAGGAAGAAACAGGCUCAAGAAACCCAUAUGUGAUGGGGAGCUCCUAACAGGCUUCCCUGGGCCACAGGAAUGGGCUCGGGCUCUCUGCUGGGCUCUGUCACCUGGCUCCAUGUGCUGCUCACCUCGGCCUUCUGAGUUUAGUAGGAUGGCAGCUAGUCUUCCCUAUUGACAGGUGAAAAAGCAGGUCCACAGCUGUUGAGUGACUUUCCCAAGGCCACACAGACCACAAAUCCUGGCUCCAAGUCCAGGGCGUUUCCAGUAAGCACUGUCCAAAUCAGUCAUGGAGGUCCCUGAGUGACAAAAAUAUGCAGGACCCCUUCUUUCCCCCUCCCAGUUCCCGCAGCUAGGCUGAGUGUUAAGAGGAAGGUGCCAUACAGGUUCAGCACCCUGGUCAGCGCCCAGCCUCCCUAAAGCCGCUGGAGGAGGCCUUUGGAGCCAGCUCAGGUCAGUGUCUGCUGCUUCCUUACCCAGGAUGGCCCACUCUUGGGGACAGACAGGCAUCCUGAGAGGAGGGGGCCUGGACCUAGGUGUCUUGCCACCCAAUACAGAGCCCUGCCCUCUCCCUCUCCUUCAGAAGGAAGUAUGGGAGCAGUUCCAUCCUCAAGGUUUCUUGGUUCCCAGGACAGAAAUUUGAGUGAGAAGCAUGUGAAGAGAGGGAUGGCCCAGGGGCCCUUGGCCAUGGUGGCCUUGGACAAGUUUGGCUUUCCCCAUCUGUAAAAUGUAGAUAAGGAUGGACCCACCUCCCCAAGAUCCUGCCUAUCUGUGAGAGUCCAUGACUAAGUGGGCCAUGGGCUGGACUGAGUUCAGUGCUCCCCCAACCUGCCCUCCUCCUCUCCCCCACAGAGCUUCCCAAUUUACAUGUAAACCUUGGGCAUCAAAGUGACAGCUGAUAGCCCAGGUUUGCCCACAAAUGUGCUCUGACUGGCGUGCAUGUUAUUAAAUUUGAUAAGAUGCAUGAUGGCA